CUUCUCUUACCGCCAUCUUGGCUCCUGUGGAGGUGAGUGAAGGGUCUGCUGCUGAAAUUUGGGGGCAAAUAACCGGAGUAGGUUUGUUCCUGUGCCUUGGCGAGUCGCCGGCCUGCUGGGAACGGGACUUCUAAAAGGAACUAUGUCUGGAAGGCUGUGGUCCAAGGCCAUUUUUGCUGGCUAUAAGCGGGGUCUCCGGAACCAAAGGGAGCACACAGCUCUUCUUAAAAUUGAAGGUGUUUACGCCCGAGAUGAAACAGAAUUCUAUUUGGGCAAGAGAUGCGCUUAUGUAUAUAAAGCAAAGAACAACACAGUCACUCCUGGCGGCAAACCAAACAAAACCAGAGUCAUCUGGGGAAAAGUAACUCGGGCCCAUGGAAACAGUGGCAUGGUUCGUGCCAAAUUCCGAAGCAAUCUUCCUGCUAAGGCCAUUGGACACAGAAUCCGAGUGAUGCUGUACCCCUCAAGGAUUUAAACUAACGAAAAAUCAAUAAAUAAAUGUGGAUUUGUGCUCUUGUAUUUUUAAGUGGAUUAAAAAACUUACUACCUUAAAUUGAUUUGCUACAUGCUUAAAAUGAUAGAGGUUGCUCAGCAUUUUUGGAGUACAAGGGGGUCAGAGAGACAUGUGAUGAAAAUUACAGGGCGAGUACAGAGAUUUAGAAGGGAACGGGUUUUAAUGCGAGUAUCUUUGACAGAGUCUUGCUCUGUUGCCCAUGCUGGAGUGUAGUGGUGCUCGCUGCAGCCUCACAUUCAAAGGCUCAAGCAAUCCUCCCUUGGCCUUUGAAGUAGCUGGGACCACAGGCUCAUGCCACCAUCCCUGGGUCAUUUUUAAAUUUUUUGUAGAGAGGGUCUGACUCUUGCCUAUGCUGGCUUCAAACUCCUGGGCUCAAGCAAUCCUCCUUCCUUGGCCUCUCCUGAAGUGCUGGGAUACAGUUAUGAGCCACCACACCUGCCAAGUGCUUUGUGAUACUAUGCAUUUGUUCAAUGCAGAUUGGGAAACUUAAAAUUUGAAUGGAGAUUAUGUUGAUGGGCUUUGGCAGUUCAUUUGGAUAGACUGGGAUGAGAAGCUCUUGGGACUUGUGACUGGACAAAGCAUUCCAGUAUAUUAAAAUAAAAUUAAGCCAUAUUACUCCACUCAUAAAAAGCAAUCCUAUGGUAGGUACAUGGAGGUUGGGAAUAGUGCACGGAAAGGUGGCAGCUUUCUUUGGCUUCAUGUUUUAAUCUGGUAAAGUUCAAGAUUGCACUUUAAGCAGGCCUCCUAAAUAUUUUAGAUUUCUUGGGGAUAUGCUAAAAUAAAACAACUAAGGCAUCA